CCAGCUCACGUCUUCCCCACCCCAGCAUGGCCGCGUGCACCAUGUCCGUCUGCUCCAGCGCUUGCUCUGACUCCUGGCGAGUGGACGACUGCCCAGAGAGCUGCUGUGAGCCCCCCUGCGGCACCGCCCCCUGCCUGACCCUGGUCUGCACCCCAGUGAGCUGUGUGUCCAGCCCCUGCUGCCAGGCGGCCUGUGAGCCCAGCCCCUGCCAAUCAGGCUGCACCAGCUCCUGCACGCCCUCGUGCUGCCAGCCGGCUUGCUGCGCCUCCUCCCCCUGCCAGCAGGCCUGCUGCGUGCCCGUCUGCUGCAAGCCUGUGUGCUGCCUGCCCACCUGCUCUAAGGAUUCCUCUUCAUGCUGCCAGCAGUCUAGCUGCCAGCCAACUUGCUGUGCCUCUUCCUCCUGCCAGCAGUCCUGCUGUGUGCCUGUCUGCUGCAAGCCCGUGUGCUGUGUGCCCACCUGUUCUGAGGAUUCCUCUUCAUGCUGCCAGCAUUCUAGCUGCCAGCCGACUUGCUGCACCUCCUCCCCCUGCCAGCAGUCCUGCUACGUGCCUGUCUGUUGCAAGCCUGUCUGCUGCAAACCCAUCUGCUGUGUGCCCGUCUGCUCUGGGGCUUCCACUUCAUGCUGCCAGCAGUCUAGCUGUCAGCCGGCUUGCUGCACCACCUCCUGCUGCAGACCCUCCUCCUCCGUGUCCCUCCUCUGCCGCCCCAUAUGCAGGCCCGCCUGCUGCCUGCCCAUCUCCUCCUGCUGUGCCCCUGCCUCCUCCUACCAGGCCAGCUGCUGCCGCCCGGCCUCCUGCGUGUCCCUCCUCUGCCGCCCCGCGUGCUCCCCCCUGGCCUGCUGAGGCCUCUGCUCAGGCCAGGAGUCCAGUUGCUGAUGUGCACAUCCCCCAGGGCCAACUGGUCCUGACUCGGGUUAGGAGGUUGCCCCCGCUUGGGACGGGGCCCCCAUGUGCUGAGGUGACCCCCCCCUCCAUACUCCCAGGAAUCUCCAUCCUCGAAGCUCCCCAGCUCCUGCCUCCCAGCAGGGGCCCACCUGCCUGUUGGGUCCCCUGUCCUCCCUCCCAGCUUCUCUGCCCCAUGUCACUUGGCCUCGACUUGAACCUGUCAGCACCUCCUCCUGCUCCCCAAUAAACUCCCCUUGGUCGCCUGA